AAACAUUUGCCAGCCAGGCUAGUGACAGAAAUGGAUUCGAAAUAUCAGUGUGUGAAGCUGAAUGAUGGUCACUUCAUGCCUGUCCUGGGAUUUGGCACCUAUGCGCCUGCAGAGGUUCCUAAAAGUAAAGCUUUAGAGGCCACCAAAUUGGCAAUUGAAGCUGGCUUCCGCCAUAUUGAUUCUGCUCAUUUAUACAAUAAUGAGGAGCAGGUUGGACUGGCCAUCCGAAGCAAGAUUGCAGAUGGCAGUGUGAAGAGAGAAGACAUAUUCUACACUUCAAAGCUUUGGUGCAAUUCCCAUCGACCAGAGUUGGUCCGACCAGCCUUGGAAAGGUCACUGAAAAAUCUUCAAUUGGAUUAUGUUGACCUCUACCUUAUUCAUUUUCCAGUGUCUGUAAAGCCAGGUGAGGAAGUGAUCCCAAAAGAUGAAAAUGGAAAAAUACUAUUUGACACAGUGGAUCUCUGUGCCACAUGGGAGGCCGUGGAGAAGUGUAAAGAUGCAGGAUUGGCCAAGUCCAUCGGGGUGUCCAACUUCAACCGCAGGCAGCUGGAGAUGAUCCUCAACAAGCCAGGGCUCAAGUACAAGCCUGUCUGCAACCAGGUGGAAUGUCAUCCUUACUUCAACCAGAGAAAACUGCUGGAUUUCUGCAAGUCAAAAGACAUUGUUCUGGUUGCCUAUAGUGCUCUGGGAUCCCACCGAGAAGAACCAUGGGUGGACCCGAACUCCCCGGUGCUCUUGGAGGACCCAGUCCUUUGUGCCUUGGCAAAAAAGCACAAGCGAACCCCAGCCCUGAUUGCCCUGCGCUACCAGCUACAGCGUGGGGUUGUGGUCCUGGCCAAGAGCUACAAUGAGCAGCGCAUCAGACAGAACGUGCAGGUGUUUGAAUUCCAGUUGACUUCAGAGGAGAUGAAAGCCAUAGAUGGCCUAAACAGAAAUGUGCGAUAUUUGACCCUUGAUAUUUUUGCUGGCCCCCCUAAUUAUCCAUUUUCUGAUGAAUAUUAACAUGGAGGGCAUUGCAUGAGGUCUGCCAGAAGGCCCUGCGUGUGGAUGGUGACACAGAGGAUGGCUCUAUGCUGGUGACUGGACACAUCGCCUCUGGUUAAAUCUCUCCUGCUUGGUGAUUUCAGCAAGCUACAGCAAAGCCCAUUGGCCAGAAAGGAAAGACAAUAAUUUUGUUUUUUCAUUUUGAAAAAAUUAAAUGCUCUCUCCUAAAGAUUCUUCACCUACUUUGGUCUCCAUAACUUCUAUGUUUUCUUUCCUUCUGACACACUAGUGCCCCUAAAUUGUGAUUUGCCUAUACGUUUAGGGCCGGGGUUGGAAGAUGUUAACAACCAUUUAAGAUUCAUUUCUGCAGUGGGAGUGGGUGGAGUUUCACCCUCUGGGAAAGGGGCAGGUGACAGGUAUUUAUCAGUCAGUGCCUCUCUAGCUCUUGUAGGAAGAAGCACACGCAGGAUGGAGUCUAGAGGAUGAGCGAUAUUGACUAGCAAUUCAUGGGCUCCCUCCAGCAGUGCGAGGGUCAGAGUUUCUGGAGCCUUGGGAGGAGGCAUCCCUGUGAGGGGGGGUUAGGGAGAUGGGAGGGCACCAGGAAAAGUGAUUAGAAGUCAGGUAUGGGAAGGCUAAAUAGGACAGAGUCGAGUACAUCUCUGCUUGGAAAAACAUAUCAACACCCUUUUUUUUGAACAUUAUAUCUUGCUCAUAAAAGAAAACUUUCCACAUUGUUUUAACAAACCCCACAGCUGAGAGUCAGGCCUGAAUCUUUGAUGUGUGCCCAUUCACAACGUUGACCCUAUUGGUUUGUGGUGGGGCAGGGCAUCAAAGACAUCAUUGACUAAUCACAUUCCCCUGAAUAGCUCAUAUUUAGAAAAUAUUCUUAGAUUCUAAAAAUGUACUAUUAAUUUGUGAUAUUCAGUCUUUUAAAUAUUUUAUACAUUAAACAGGCAUAGUUACAAAUAUAAAACAAAAAUAUCCCAAAGCCAUUAUGCAUGGCACUCAAGAUUAAAAUGGGAAAUAAUACAUCUAAUAAAUCAAAUGUUCCAAGACUUCAAAGGUCUUUUGGAAACAGGCUAUGUAAAACAGCACACUGGUUUCAAACUUUGGUAAAUUUUAAGAACAACUCUUACAAAGGCAUUUAAUUCUUAUACAUAAUUUUCAGGGGACCUAAGUUAAUCAGCUAAUCAUGAAGACAUGAUUUUCAUUUUAGAAAACACUUUUGAAAACUUGGGAUAAUCUCAUGCCUUAAUGAUCAAAGCAUUAUGAGAAGGACAGUGGUUUUUAACCUGGGCAUAUGUUCUAACACAUUUACUCUCCACUAUUCGUACUCUGGUAGCCAUGUUAACCCCAUCAGAGAUUCCUUCUCAAGCCAUGUCUCAGAGCUGAGAGGCAUCCCAGCAAGUUUUGCAGCUCACAGUUUUUUCCGUAAAUUACUUAUUCUAUAAAAUUGGAGUAGGCCAUAAACUUUGGAGGGCCCUAGACCAAUUUUUUGGAUUAUUUUUCGUCUUCUAUCAUUCCGCUGAUCUUAGAUAUUCUCUGCAUUAAAUAUUAAAUAUCACUUCUAGGCUGAAAAAUCCCCCUAAAAAUAUUUCUAGCUCAGAUUUUUCCUCCAAAUUCUGCAAUAGAAGAUCACAAUGUGAACUCUGCAUCUCCAUGUUAAAGUCUAAUGGACAUUCACACUUAGCAUGUCUCAAAGAAAUCUCAUGUAAACCAUGGCCAUCCUGUUCUACCUUAACUUUCUGAGUCUAUGGAAUGAUAAUUUCACAUCUCAUAAACUUGACUGAUGUAAGUGUCAAGAAAAGAUUGACAUUUUGUUAAAAGUUAGUAGUGAAGUGUGUAACGCUUAAGCAAACUUUCAUAUUUCAAAUCUCUUUAGCAAGUGUAACUCUUUUUUCAAGAUGUGAAAUAAUCAUUAGGUCAGUCAUUUGUAAAUAGUACAUCUGCUAUGGACUUUUUCCAGUUCUUCACCAUCCAUUUUUAUAAAACUCUUAUUGUUAAAAAAAAAGUUACUCAGAAUUUCAUAAAGCCAAACACCUGAUUUCAGGAACACUUGAGAUGUAAGAAAAUUUUAUAGGGACCUCCAAUCACUAAUUUUCCUAUUUUUUCUCUCAAAGAAAUGCUGAAGGGAGGAAUUCAGGUUGAAUGAAAGGAAAUAGUAACUUACAGCCAUAUAGAGUUAUAAAGACUUCUUGUAAAUGUGAACAUAUGGUAAAAUAUAAAAACAUGUAUUUUUGAAAUUUUGGAUUCUACUCAUUAUUUUACUUCAAUUUAAGAUAUAAAUGUAUAGAAAUAAGUAUAAUUCUAAGCUAAUACGUAUGCAAUGUAGGAAGCUGUAAUUACUGACCAAAACUAUGUGAAGUGGAGAAAACCUGGGGAAGUGGAUGGUUUUAGAUGAAACUGAAGUUAAAUUCAUAUUGAUUUAAAGUAAAUUGUUAUAACUUUAUAAAGUUUUUCAUCAUCACCACAGCAAUCACAAAGAGAAUAAUUAUGAAUAUACGCAAGAGGAAAUGAGAAGGGAAUCCAAAUGUCAUUAAAAAAAAAUCACGCCACCUCACAAAAUGGUAACAGUGGAUAUAAAGGAUAGAAAGCUAUAAACCUGGUAGGAAAACAUUGAAAAUGGCACAAGUGACUCCUUCCCUGUCACCAAUGACAGUCAUGUGUUGCAUAAUGCCUGGGCUAUCUUCUGAGAAUGGCUUUGUUAGGCAACUGUGUCAUGGUGGGGACAUGAUAGCAUUAGAGAGAAUUCUCUCAAACACUGUCAUGGCCUUAUCAACUAUGCUUCUGUAAUAUUCUGAAUCCUUCGCUGCCUUUCCAACAGUGUUUACAACGGUUUCCUAAGAAAUGAAAUCCAUUUCACCAAACCACUUUUCUUGCUCAUCCAUAAGAAACACUUCUCCUUUGUUAAAAUUACAUCAUGAGAUUGCAAGCAUUCAGUAACUUGCAAGCUCCAAUUUGAAUUCUAGUUGUCUUGCUAUUUCCACCACAUCUGCAAUUACUUUCUCCACUGAAAUCUUGCAUUCCUCCAAGUCAUCCAGGAGGGUUGAAUUCACUUCUUUCAAACUCCUGUUCAAGUAAAUGUUUUGCCCUCCUGUCACGAAUCAUGAAUGUUUUUAAUGGCAUCUAGAAUAGUAAAUCUUUUUCAGAAGAUUUUCAAUUUUCUUUUCCCAGGUUCUUCAGACAAGUCACCAUGGUAGCUGUAGACUUAUGAAAUGUAUUUCCUGAACCAUAAAACAAGAACAUCAAAAUUACUCUAUGAUCCAUGGGAAACAGAAUGCAUGUUGUGUUAGCAGGCAUGGAAAGAACAGUAAUCUCUUUCAACCUCUGUAAGAGAGUUCUUGGUUGAUUAGGUACCUUGUCGAUAGGCAGUUCUAAUUUCAAAGAACUUUUUCUUUUGCUGAGCAGUAAGUCUUAACAGUGGGCUUAAAAUAUUCAGUAAACCAUUAUUUAAGGAGAUGUGGCUUAAAUAUCUAGGCUUUCUUGCUUUAUUUAUAGAACACUUACAGAGUAGAUAUAGAUUAAAUCUUAAGGACCCUAGGAUUGUUAGAAUAGUAAAUGAACAUCAUAUGUUGUAAUAUAGUUAGCCAGGGAGGGGAAAGAUCUCUACAAGAAAUAAUUUUAAAAACUACUCAAAGAAAUCAGAGAUAUCACAAAAUGACAAAACAAGUACAGGGGCAGCAAAAGGUAACAGAUGUCAACUAUGAGAUCUCAUCAAGAACUAAGAAAAUGGAGAAAAGUACCAGAUGGCAGAUGGGAGGCAGUGUGAGCAUGCCUCUCCCACUUGGAGAUUAGUGUGUAGAGAUUUACAUUGUGAAUUUCUUUUCAAGAACCAAUGCAGAGACUUAACAGAUAUAUGAAAAAAUUUCACAUACACUCUGAAGAAGUCUCAGGCACAAUCCUACUCCAUGAAAUAAGAAAAAACCAUCACAUCCCCAGAUUCUGAGGGGAGAGAGUUCACUCCAGAGCAUACAUCCCCACUGGGGAUCUGGAAAUUCAGGCCACAAGAGAAGGCUUUGAUCCUGUGCGGACAAGUGCCUUGAGCAGAAUCCACAGGGGAGAGCUGGAAGUGCAUGGCAGAUAUGAGCACAGAAGCUGGGUGUCCAGCCUUGUGGGCAGACCGGGAGGGAUGUGGCCUGAAAGCCAUGGUUAUUAUCUCAGCGUGUAAGCUGAUGAUCUGAGGCUGGUCAGAGUUCUGUGCGCAGACUGCCUGGAUGUAAACCUGGCACUGUUAGCAGAGCACUGCAUGAAUGAAAGGAAUGAAAAUAGCCUUGCCAACUGCAUAGGUGCUGGGUGAGGCUCACUGUGGGGGGCGCACGGCAAGCUAUUCAACAUUACGUACAGGCAUUUGAGGUCGGGGCAUGGAAAAAUACUGAGGCAGUGUGUGUAUGUUAUUUGUGCUGAGAAUGAAACUCCUUGACCUUGAAAACAGGACAGGGAGUGGUGUGUGUGCUGUGAUAAGGAAUGCUGAAAACGGUCUCCUGAGAAUGCGGUUUGAGUGCUUUUACAAGGCCACAGGUGUCUCACGACCUGACCUCAUAAAGCCAUCUAGUGGAUGUUUGUGGCUUAACAAGCCCCUUCAAUAAGUACUUGGCGGAGGGAUGCUGGGGGGACCUUCUUAGAAGAGCUGCGCCCCACCCCCCUCCCUGGACAGCCCAGCUACAAUUGUCUGAGAACUCACUGCAAGCUGUAAGCGGCCCACUACUUCCCACUCCCUUUUUUGAACUCUUCUGUGCAGCAGAGGCAAUUAAACUCUCCUCUGGAACAUUACCCCAGCAGCCUGAGAACCACCCCUUGGCGCUCACAGGGGCUGCAGCCUGCCUUAUCCAAGGACAGUUAGAGUGCAGACCCACCUAACCCUGGACCCACUGGUGGUACCCAUCCACCCAUCCUGGUAGCUUAACACAAAGAUACACUUUUAGGAGCUUCAUAGCCCCUCUUCCCCCAUUGCCUGAGAAACCACUUUCCCUGGGCAACUUAGGGCAAGCUCAAAUCCCACUGCUACCACCACAGCUGGUGCUCUUUUGCAAGUGCCACCUCCUAGCUGGAGACCAACCAGCACAGUCCACACAGCACCUCAAGGAAGAAUAAAUAGAACUGUUCCCAGGAAGGAGAAAAUGCCUGCAUGAGCUCAGCUGUUACCACUGCGUACCACACCCUGACCAGUCAGAGGUCUUGAGUCGGUCCGCAUGACAAGUUCACCGCUCGCAUAACCAGCAUUCAAGAAAGCCAGCACACUAAGCCUAUCUACAGCCAGGGAGUCUCAGAGUCUACGUCACUCCCCUGCCACCUCAAUCAGAGCUGGUGCUGGUAUCCACUGCUGGGAGACUUGUGCUGAGGUGAAGCCUGGGCUGGAUGGCUGGAGGAUGAAGAACUGCACGGAGGAGAUGGAGGCACCCAGACAGAUGCCCCAUGGACAUCCUGAAGCAGAGCUGCCUCACUGCCCUGCACACACAUGAGAGCGCAGCCAGGAACAGAAGGACUGGGCAACAUUCAGGCGGAGCCCAGGCCAAUUUUCUAAACAUGGAAUAUGAGUUAAAUAAAUGGCUUCGUAUUAAA